GGCAUUACUGGUGGUUUCUCCUGCCUGCAGUAAGCUUUCCAGCUUACUCUAGACUCCUGUGCUGUGAGACAUGAGCUUGUCAGAGGUAAGGAGCCUGUGUUAAUGCAAGUCUCAGGUGAGAAGGGGUGUUGGAAUCUGAGGACCCUGUUUUCCUUCCUGUCCCCUCUUCAGCUCUGUCCAGGCACCACCCGAUGGAGGGUUGGCUGAAUGUCUCAUGUUCAUAUACCUGACAGCUGGCUUCGGUGCUUUAAUAUUUAUGGAAAGGACAGUUAUAGAAGUGUGGUCCCUUCAAAGUAGUCCUCUGGGGUGUCUGUGUCCUUAUUAGGUUGACUUCUGAAACUUCCUGUGAGAAUUCCAUCAUUAAACUUUGGCUUUCUCUGGAGGGGUAAAUCUUUGUUCUUUGGAGUAGGAUUUGAGUUUGACAAGGAGCUGGACAAUGCUGUUUGGAGUCAGAGAUGCAGUGUGAUAAGAGAGCUGUGAGUUGGAAUUCCACAGCACCUAAAGAGACUCCUAGAAAAUGUUGUAGAACAAGUGGCUGGAUGGUACUUGGUUGCACAUACGGGGUUUGGGGUCUGUGCAGAAAAAUGACCAAAUCCAAGCAGCCUCUGAGAUUAUGACCACAUGGGGGCUGUUAAGCUGUGGAUCUGAGUCAUAGGGUCAGGGAAAGAGGAAAAAUGGCAAGGAGGAUGACGUUACUGCCCAUGAGCUUAUCCUCUGAGUGGGUGGCGACUUCUCAUUGUCCUUUUCCCACAUCCCCAGGGCAGGAGUGUUAGGGAAGUCCACCAGCAAAAGGGGGAGGGCACACCCAGGGCCUAGGGGAGGGGGAGAGGGGUGAGGACUGGUCCACAUGAUUUUUGAGAAAUUGCCUUUGGUCUUGUUGGCUCAGAAUGGACCCCACACCUGGAAGGGGGCCACGUGUACAGUUAUGCAACCCUUGCCUGCCACCCCCAGUUCUACCGCCCUUGCAGUGUGCCAGAUAGGAGCAUUGGGUUUUCAGGUUUGGGAGUGGGUAGGGUUGUGCUGGAGGCUAAAUAGACAUUAUCUCAUGUAAUCCUCAUAGUAAUCCUAUGAGGUAGGGUAUCAUUAACACCAUUGUACAGUUGGGGAAACUGAGGCCCAGAAAGGGUAAGUCACAUGCCCAAAGACACACAGCCGGCAAAUGGUGGAGCUGGGCUGUUGUCUGCUUCCAGAACUGGCUUUUUCUGCUGCUCUGGAGGUAGGCACAGGUUUUACCCCUCUUUCUGGAGCCCGGUAAGAUGUGCCAAGGGUCUCCUUAGUAAGUCAGGGAAGACUCAUCUGGGGAACCAGAGAAGGGGCAGGCCUGACCUGGGUGACCCAGUGACUAGUGGCCUUCACAGCAUAGUCAGGGCCUUUGCUGAGAGUUCUUCUCUUCCAGAGCCCUGGACUUUAUCAUGCUGGGGCUUCCAGGAGUUCCCCCUCCACCCUCCAGUUCUGACCAGUGCUCCCAGCCAGCUGCCCCCUUUCUCCCUUUCUUUCUCUUUGUGGUCCAGAGAAUGAAUGCCUGCUCCACACACCUUAUGCCAUUGGGAAUCUGACCUUCUCUAGGCAUAGGGAGCUUAAUCUGCGGGAAGUGGAGUGAGAAGCAUUUCUUGCUGGGAGCCUUGGAGCAGGGAGAGAUACUGUCUCUGGGAGGCAGGGGUCCCAAGUUACCCUAGAGGCAAUGCAGGCUCCUAGGAACUGGGGCUGCCUUGUGGGAGACAUUGGAAUGUGUCCCUGUGGGAAUGCUCUGUGCUAGGGGCUAUGGCAGCAGGACGGUAGGAGCUCAUGGUACUUGGAACUGUGACCAAGCAUCUGCGAAGAGGAAGGGGCCCAGGACCACUAGAAUGAGUCAGAGCCAGAGAUGGAGUCGAGUUGUGCAUUUGCUACUUUGGAGCUGGGGCACUGAUAGGGCUCUAGGUGAAAAGUAGGGAUACAGAAGGAGUAAUGGUCCCAGAGGCCCAGAUGUGUGGCCUGACAGAGGAGGUCUUGGCCAGGGAGAGUGGGGUAGGGGCAAAGUGUUCGCUCAGUGCAGAGGCCCCAUCUAGGAGGCCUUGUCCCCAUGCUUGCGGCAAUAAUAACAGCAAUAAUAAUAAUUAUUACUGCAGUUUUGGUACUGGGCACUUUCCUAAGUCCUCUCUCUCUAUUGUCUUAUUUUAUUCUCACAGCAGCCCUGUGGGGUAGGGAUUGUUACCCCCAUUUUAGAGAUUUGGAAUUGGGUCUCAAAUAGGUUAAGUCAUUUAAACUUGGUCAUGUGUUCAGCAAGGCAUCGGUGUCAGGAUUGAAACCCAAGGCUGCUGGCUUCUGAGCUCAUGCUGUACCCUGGGCAGGCAAGGCAGCCUGGUGAUUCCAUUCAAUAAGUGAGGAAGAGAGAUAGGAGCAUCAGCUGGCUCUUAGUCACUUCUGCUGGUGGCUGAUAAUUGAGUGUGGGCCCUUGGCCAGCCGGCCACCACUCUGGGUCCAGAUUUCCAUCUGUACAAUGGGCCUGGAGCUAGGCGCUGGACCAGGUGUACCGUAAGAGGCCUUCUAGCUCUGAGGACUGGUGGAGAUUGCUACACUCCGAGAGGGGUCUGGUGCUUAGAUGGAGAGGGGUCGGCAGAGUUGUUCUGCUAAGCUGAGCCUCUUUCAGGGUAGAAACCAAAGGAAUUUGGAGGCAAGGAGGCAUUUAGGCAGAUCACAUCUGGAGAAAAUGCACCCUUCCUUGAGUGCAGUCUGGAAAGGCUUCUGGAAAGGAUAGGAUUUCCAGAUAUGUUUAGGUGGGCACCUAGCAGGACUCAGCAGAUAUUGAGUGAAUGCAGAUGUGUGUGCCCUGGGCCUGCCAGUGUCUGACCCGAAAUCUGCGCUCUGAUGUGGUCUCAUGUGCUCUCAUCCCUUUCCUUCCUCUCCCUAUUCUCCUUGUUGCCAUCCCUUCUUUUGGCUGGACCUCCUCUGGGCCCAAUGUAGCUUUCACUUUUUUCAGGGCUCUGUGCCUCCUGUGUGUGUGUGUGUGUGUGUGUGUGUGUGUGUGUGUGUGUACACAUUUCCACAUGCAUGUAUAGGUCAGUUUUGCAGCCCCUGCACAUGCCUCUAGUUCCAGGGAGACCUUAGCCCUGCUUUGCUGGCCAGCCCUGAUGACAUACUACUGUCCUGACUCACACAGAAAUCGCUUGGAGAGGAAGAACUGAUUCCUGCUCUUGGGUGGGAUCACGGGACUGGGGAGUGGUGCCCAGUGGACAGCCUUGAACAUAAAAGGCCCAAACUGACUCAGAUUAUCAGGAAAAAGGAAGGCAAACAGGGAGGCUGUUCCCAGGGAACUCUAGGGACCCUCCCAUCUCUUUUCUGAGGCUGCUGCCCAUUUAUAGAGCACCUAGUAUUAACUAGGUCAGUUUUGAUAAUUUUGCUCAUUGAGUCCUAUAAUCAUCCUAUGAGGGUAAGGUUUAUAAUCCCCAUUUUACAAAUGAGCAAACUGAGGCUCAGAGAGGAUAUUUUCAUAAAGUUUCAUUACUAGGAAGUGACAGAGUCUGGAUUUGAACCUGUCUCUCCAACUCCAAAGUCAUCUUCUUAAACACUAGUGCUAACUUCUUCCAUGAAGCUUCUUGUGAUUACACCAGCCCAACAUGCGAUAUGGUCACAGCAUGGGAUGGUGGUCAGGACCCUUUGAUGGUUGAGGAGAUGAAGACCCAGAAAGGCAAGGGGUUUGGCCUAGGGAGCCUGGCAAGUGAGUGACAGAGCCUGGUCUAAAGUCCAGGAUAUCUCUGUUGUUGCUGUUUUCCUUUUUUCGUUAAUUGCAAAAGAAUUUACAUGUUCAUAGUUAAAAACAGAGAAGUGUAUCAAGUAGAAAACAGUAGCAAACUCUCACCCUUAUUCUGACACUCCAGAGUUGCAUUCACUCUCAGGCAUCCAGAUCCUUUCCCCAUAUACAAACAUCCAUCCAUCCAUAUAUCUAUCCAUCUCUCUAUCUAAACACACAUGCAUUCAUUCGUUCACUCAUUGAAUCGUGCAUUGAGAACCCAUUAUGUGCCAAGCCAUUGCUAGAAUUAAGGAUGCAAUAGUUAAAUAAAGCAGAUGUGGUUCCUUCUCAGGGAGGUUCUCAUAUAUCAUGAAGAAAACAGACUGGGUGCAAUGAAUGACAGGGUCCUUCUUAGAGUGGCAGAUCUCUUACCUGGCUUUUCUGUCAAGGUGACCCUCAGAAUAUGGAGGUGUUACCUUUUAUCUUAGUCCAUGUUUUACUGCUAUAACAGAAUACCACAGCCUGGGUAAUAUAUAAAGAAAAAAAGGUUAUUUGGCUUGUAGUUCUGGAGACUGGGAAGUCCAAGGGCAUGGUGCUGGCAUCUGGCGAGGGCCUUCUUGCUGCAUUAUCCUAUUGUGGAAGGGCAUGUGAGCGUGCAGUACAGACAGUAUGGGGGCAGCACUUACGCUUUUAUCAGGAGCCCACUUUUCCUGUGAUAACAGCAUUAAUCUCUUCACUUCUUACAGGCCCCACCUCUUAAUACUGUUACAGUGGCAAUUAAAUUUCAACAUGAGUCUUAAAGCACCCAUGUCAUCUAGGAAGAAGAAACUGUAUUUGCAGCAACACUGUGAGGUAGGAAAGGGAGUCCUAUGUUGUAGGAACUGGAAGCAGCCCACUGUGGUGAGGGGCAAGUAGGAAGAGGUGAGGCUGGGCAGGUGGGCAGGGCCAGGGCAGAUGGGGCUCUGUAGGCUAUGGAGGAGCUGCGAUCUUAUCACAAGGAAAGUGAACAGCCCUAUGAUUAACUAUUGAAGGCAGUGAUAUAAUUUAUGCUUUUAUAUUAAUAGCAAUUAUUCUGGCUGUUGUAUAGAGUAUAGAUUGGAGAACAGAAUUGGGUGGGGGAACUAGAGAAGGUGAACAGACUGGUGAAGAGGCUUUUAUAGUUAUCCAGGCAAGAGAUGAUGGUGACUUGGAAGACCAGGAAGAGAAGCAGGGGUAGAGAGAAAUGGAGAUAGUGAAGAUAUAGCAGACAUAUUUGAGGAGUCCUUCAGUUACAGAUAAUAGAAAACUAGCUCAAGCACAUUUAAGAAAAAAAAAAAAGACUUGUUUAAGUACCUAGGCAGUCUAUGUGUGCAGCUUGCUUCAGGAAUAGGGGCUUAAAUGAUGGUUUUAGGGCUCUAUAUCCUUCUAGCUUCCAUCUCUGCCUCUGUUCAUUUGUUUGGAUCAAUUCUUUAGAUUGUUGGUAGCAGACACAUUUAUUGCUAACAGUCCCAGACCGUAUCCUUCUUAGUAAUCUCAACAAGAAAGAGUCUUUUUUGAUGGCUGCAGCAGCAAGGCUCUGGGGAAGUCUCUGAUUGGGUGUGGCUUGGCUUACAGCUCAUUCUCGAACUAAUCACUGAGUGGGGGCAGGGCAGGUUUCUCCAUGAGCCAGGUCUUGUAACAUGCCCAGGCCCUAGGCUGGGAGGACAGCUCCACCAGUACAGCAUGGACUGGGCUCCCUGCAGGAGUGCGGAGCCUUGCUACCAGAAGGGGCCAGCAUAGACCAAGAGAAGGGCACUGUAGAAUAAAGGACAUGGAGCAAAAUAACUGUGUUAAGACUAGCUACCAAAGACGGAGACGAUCUGCUCGGCAUUGAAUUUGCCUCUUUGUCAAGGAAAGAAGGAGCAGAAGAUGUUAAGAAGGAAUUGAAGUUUAGGCCAUACGGGGAGGUGCUCAUCUGUUUUAACUGUAUUUGUCUUCUGGCCCCUGGGAUUGCCUGUCCUGGUGUGGGGUGAACUUGGAGACAGAAUCUCUGAGAAGCUGUCAGGGAUAUUUCAGGCCAGUCUAGGGUAGAAGAGGGUUGGACACGUGGGUCACAGUAUUCCACAGUUUCCUGCUGUGCACAGAUUCAAUCCGAGUCCCCAUCUACGUCCCUCACUACCUCCCUUGCCUCCUCUCCUGAGUCUCAGCCUCUCCUGGAGUCCCAUCUUCCCAGAAUAUGCUGUGGACAUCUCCUCUUCUGUGACUUUUCAUGCUGUCCCCUCCGCCAGAUAGCCGAGAUGUCUCCUCCUCUGUGCAGUCCUUACUGAGCCUCCCCAGCCCCCAGUGAAUGGCUUGACCCUUUCAUCCAGGUUUAAGCCUACUGCCUCGUCCAUUCCCACAAUACCUUGUAUAAAUGUGUACCAAAAAACUGGUCAUAUUCUAUUUUAAUGAUAUAUUUGUUUCCUAAACCUUUUUUCUAUUUUUAAUAUGAAAAUGUGGGAUUUUAAAUAUGCCAUUUAGCAGCUCUGUAAUCUUGAGCAAGUUAUUAAAUCUCUCCAUCCCUGAAUUUACUCCUCGGUGAAAUAGGAUAAUAAUAGUACCUACUUCACAGAAUUGUUGGGAAGCUUAAAUGAGUUAAUAUGUGUAAAAGCAUUUAGAACAGAGCCUGGUGCAUGGCUUUCAACAAAACUGGCCUAUGUUAUUAUUAUUUGAUAAAAGCAAAAUAAUAUAUAUAACAUGGGUAACUUUUGAAGCAUAAUAAUAAACAUACCUCCCAACUUGAGAAUGAGAACCCCUGUAGUUGAAUAUUUAUAUGUACGAUUCUUCAUCUCCAUUCAUAUUGCAUGCAUGGCCAAUGCCUGGCAUGUGGAUCAUGAAUAAGCAUUUGUUGAAUGAAUAAAUGAACAAAUGCCAGAAGACUUGAGACAGGGAAAUAACCAGUUUUAUGGGGAAGAUGGUAGAUUAUGGGAACAACAGAUCGAUAAUCUUGUUCUUAAUCCUUGACAAAGUCCUGGAACCAAUGAGCACUUGAAGAAGAGCCCACUAGUAGGCACUUGCAUGGCUUCACUGGGGUUUUGAAAAUGCACUUCUUUUCUUGUUCUUCUCCAGUUGAUUGGUCCCCAGCCAGAAGCAGUGAAGCUUCUCAUGACAGCCCUGGGGAUGAGAUGGGUAGAUGGGAGCUGGGUAGCAGCACAGGUAGGAACACUCCUAACCCCGGUGUACUGAAUGGUGGAUGGACAUUGAUCAUCCAGGGACAGAUGGUGCUGUGGGCUUUCCUAUUCCUGUCCUCUCCCUGAGGACCUUGAUGACACCCAGACACCAGCAGAGAGAGGAGAGUAACCUUUUCAGAUGAUAUUCAUUCAUUCUUUUUUUAAUCCACCAACAAAUUAUUGAGCAUUGUCUAUGCACCAGAACAGUCAAAAGAGUACUUCAAAAGAUCACGACAGGGUUACACAGCAUUGUAAAUAUAGUUAAUGCUGCCGACUUAUACACUUAAACCUGGAUAAAAUGGCCAACUUCAUGUUAUAUAUAUUUUACAACAAUGAAAAAAAUGUUGUGGCAGUUGGAGGAAUGGACUCAGUUUAACUGGGUGAAAUGGAAUAGUAACAAAUGAAAUAUCCUGUAAAACUCCUCCCCAUUCUGAACUCCAUCAGAAGAGGAUGGCAGAGGUGUGGAUUAGCAGCAAUGAGUGUGAGUGACUUCUGAUGGUUGGCUACAGAUUUGAUAGUCUGUUAUUUUGGGUUAUUUUGGUGAAUGGUGUGACAUGGCUGCUCAAUGGUGACUUCGUCAAGGAAGAUCAAAUACUUGCAGGGCUUUGAUAAGGAAGGGGGCAGACUCAUUCUGUGUGGUCCAAGGGGUCACAUGAGGACUGUUGUGGGCUGUAUUGGGAGACAAAUUUGGGCUAAGUAUAAGGUAGAGCUUCUCACCGAUGAACGCUGUCCAAAAGCAAGUGGAUAGCCCAUGCAGGCCAUGGGUGCCCAUCACGGGAGGGCAAACAGAGAUUGUGUGUAUGCGGUGGGUGGGGGGAGGGGCAGGGAAAGGUUCCCUGUUCUGAUACUUGAUCAUUAAUUUCUGCAGUUUCCCCAGAAUUUGUUCUCAUGGCAUCAUCUCCCUCAGUGACCCCACCUUUGGUUCUGUCACCACCACUGCACGAAUGACUGCCAUGUCCCUCUGUUCUGAGCUGCAGCUCAGUGUGUCUGGGAGUCCAUAGGACAUUUUGGUGUGGAUGAUCCAUAGUCGAGCUCAGUAGGAACUGAUCUUCCCCCUCCACGUGCUUCAUCUCCAGGUCUCCUUGUUAUGUGUGUCCAUGUUUGCCCAUUGCUCAAGCCUUCAGUGCCCUCUUGACACCUUCAGCCCCUCCCUCAAUACAAACAGUCCCCAAGCCUGGUCACUUCUACCCUUGACAUUUGUCCAAAGCUGGGCUCAGGCAUCACUCGGUGACUCUGAUGAGAUAGUCUCCUGUUCGUAUUUUGAGAUACCUAUUUUAGAUGUGGUUUCCUUUUGUGGCUCUGAGCAGUGGCAAUGCUCAUCGGGUACGGAGACGGGGAAGAGAAGGAGGGAAAGUAAGGGUGGGAUGGCUCCUUAGUUAGUUCAGAUGCUGUAAGAAAGGCCCAAAAUAGCAAUGACUUAUGCUGGAAGAGAUGUUUAUUUCUCACCCAUGUGACCAUCUGGGUAUAUCCAGGGCUGAUACUACAGUCCCUCAGGGUUCUUCUGUCUGCUGCUCUGCCGUCCUCAGGGUGUUGCCUUUGGCAGUAUGAUCGCCACACACACCACAUCUAUGUUCCAGCCAGUGGGAAGGGGGAGGGGAAAGGGAGGGGAGGGCAUGCUUCUCUCUUUCAGGGCAUGACCCAGAAGCUGUACACAUCAGUGUACACAUUGCAUGGCCACACUCAGCUGCAAGUAAGGCUGGGAUCUGCAGUCGUUAGCUGAGUGGCCGUGUGCCUAACUAAAAAUGCUAUGGAAGAAGGGGAGAGCUGGGUGUGCUGGCAGCACCUGUAGUCCCUGUUACUCGGGAGGCUGAGGCAGGAGGAUCACUUGAGCCCAGGAGUUACAAGGGUGCAGUGGGUUCUGAUUGCACCACUGAACUAUGAUGGUACCACUCCAGCCUGGGUGACAGAGCGGGACCCUGUCUCUUAAAAAGGGAGAAAAUGGGUGUAAGUGGACAACAACUAGCAGUUUCUGCCACAGUCACUUUGUGCAUUUCAGUGGGAACUGUGUGGCUGUGAACUGGUUAAGCCUUAAGGAUAUAGUCCCUGAAAGCUUCAAGUACUGAUAAAGUUCCACUAGCAUCCACAAAGCUUUUCUUUUAUAGGUAGGAACACUGAGCUCAGAGAAGUUGCCUAGUUAAGAUUGCAUAACAAAGUGUCAGAGCUGGGACCAGAACCCCACACUUUGGGCUCAUUUUCUAGAAUUCCAGGGUGAUCUGGCUGAGGGGCAGACAGGCAGUGUCAGGAGGACGGGUCUCUGGAGUUCAGGAAAGGGUUACCUUUCCCAGCGCGGCUACCUGGGGAGCUGCUCAUGACUUUUCAGGGAUCAUCUCUGGGGUUAUCAUGCCUCUGAGGUGCCUCCAAUUCGCCCUGACCAUAUCAUAAAUAGUAUACUAUACCAAACUGCAGUGAUCUAACUGCAUGUCCCCCUUCCCUAUUAGAAUCUGCUCCUUGAGGACAGACGUGUACCUUAGUUAUCUCUCUGCCCCUAGUACGUCCCUACCAGGAACUCCGUAAGUAGUGAAAUGAAUUACUAAAGACAUGAAUGCAUGUGGAUUCAAGGACUCCUUCGGUUGCAGACAAUAGAAACUUAGUUCAAACUGGUUUAAGGGAAAAAAAAUGAUUGGCUCAAAUAUCUGGGCGGUCUAGGUCUGCAGCUUGCUUCAGGCAUAGCUGGAUCCAGGGACUUGUCUGACAUUUUCAGAACUUUGUGUCUUUCUGACCCUUUUUGUCCCUUUGUGGGAAGUGUUGCCCAAGGAGCCCCUGCGGGGAUUGGGAGGAAGUAGGGGGUUAGGAGGAAGUGGAGUGAUGUGGGUGAUUAUGGUGGGGGGCAAGGAGACCCUCUUGGGCAUCCCCAGGCCCAGGGCAUUUUGGCCCUGAGCCCAGGUGCAGUCUGGAUUUGUUGUAGCUUUCUGAGGGCACAUCUUGGGUCAUCUCUUGGGAGCCUCCCUGUGGCCCUGCUUCUGCAGGGUUGGAUGCCCUUGCUGUACCUUAGGCUGAGGACAGCCUGACCCCUCUCUCCUGCUGCUCUGUGAAAGCCGAAGGUGCUCUGUGGUUUUGGGAUAGAGCAGGAAGGAGAAGGACGAGGAGUGGGCACUGGCAGGUGACUCACCGGGACGGGUGGCACAUGCUGACUCCAGGGCAGGUCCCGGCUGGGGAUGAGAUUCCCCUUUGUGGAAAACAUGGGUGGAGGGGGUGGUACGCAGGCAGCAUGAGGCCUGCGUGGCUCCACGUGGCUCUGGGUCCCGGGCCGACCAGCUCUGUGUUCACAGGACACUCUCCCAUUCUCCAGGGAGCACUUCCUUUCUGAGCUCUGUCUCUUUCUCCUGUCCUCAGCUCCUCCAGGCCCAGCUGUCAGCGUAGGGGUCUCUGGGUGCCGUGGACUCUUCUGGUCUCUUUGCUUCUGGGCUGUCAAACUGCUUCUCUCCAGGGCAGGUUUCCAGGAUCCAGAGUCUAGGAAAGGAAUGAAAGGGAGCAAGUCCAGGGCGCAGCCCUGGAAGUCCCUCAUCUUCCCUCUGGAGGGAAGCGCAGCUCGGCCCUGGGAGAGCCUGGGUAGGUCUGAUCAGGGGAGGUGCCCUCUGCUCCCUGUACCUGCCCAGAGUGGCAGGAAUUAGCCUGAUAUAUGAAGGAGACAAUUAUAUGAAGAGUCUUGAGUACCAGGCAGAGGAAUGGGGUCUGACUUCUAUAGUGAAUGGGGAGCCAUGGGAAGUUCUUGAGCAGGGGAGGGACAUGAGCAGAUUCCUGUCUUAGGUCCUAAGAGAAGGCACCUUAGAGAAUGGGGCUGGCAGGGAAAGAGAGGAGCAAGCAGGGCCAGUGAGGGGGGUGAUGGGUCAGGGUGGGAGAUGGAAGCUUGAGAAGCAGUGUGGAGAGUGAGGGAGGCGGCCCAGGAAGAACCCACAGGCCUUGGUUCUGUCUGGGGUUAAAGAGAGGCAGGGAGAUGUGGAAUCUGGGCGUUCGUUCAUCCUUAGCCCUGGUGCUUCCCGCAGGGGUUGGGCAGGUCCUGCAGGCAGCUGCCUGCUGGAUCUUCCUGUGGGCCUCAGGGUGGCCCUUGUGGGGCAGGAUGUGGUGCCUGCCAAAGGUGCUUUAUGAAUGGAGCCGGGGAAGGCUGCUGACUCAGCAGGCAGUAAGGCUUUGAGGCCGGAAGCGUCUGGAAAGGAAGUGGCUGCUCAGGGCUUCCCCACUGUAGACAGCUGGGAGAGAAGGGGGGCUGGCCAGGAUGCACAUGGUUUGGCUGAGGGACUCCCUUGGCCCAGCUGCUGGGGGUGUGUGUGUGUAGGAGUGGAGGGUGGCGGGGGGCGGGUGUGCCUGGCUGGGAUUGGAAGGAUUGAGGCUGGGCGCCUGGAAUGGAAUUGAGGCUAGCAGCUGUUGAUGAGGUUUGCUCCGUGGAAGGGUGGAAAGGUGUAGCAGAAUUGGACUCUUUUUGGCUGUGCUGACUGGCAAAUUACUUGACAUUAACAAAGUCACUUAUCUGGGCUUUAAUUUUUUUUUUUUUUUUUUUGAGACAGAGUCUUGCAGUAUCGCCCAGACUGGAGUACAGUGGCGCGAUUUCCACUCACUACAACCUCCGCCUCCUGGGUUCAAGCAAUUCUCCUGCCUCAGCCUCCUGAGUAGCUGGUAUUACAGGCCUGAGCCACCACGCCCAGCUAAUGUUUAUAUUUUUAGUAGACACAGGGUUUCACCAUGUUGGUCAGGCUGGUCUCAAACUCCUGACCUCGUGAUCCACCCACCUCGGCCUCCCAAAGUGCUGGGAUUACAGGCAUGAGCCACCACACCCAGCCAUGGGCUUUAAUUUUUUAAAGUCCUGCAAAAAUAGGACCAAGUGUUACAGCCUAUCUCCCAGGGUAUUAGGAGGACGUGAAAUCAUUUCUAUUCUUGUUGAUCAGUGUUGGUUGGCAUAGAUGUGGCUUGAUCAGGACAUGGCACAAAUGUUUAGGCAGCAGCUGUGGGACUCAGGGACAAGGCAGGGGCAGCCUUCCACCACGGGGAGCCCAGCUGUCAGCCGCCUCACAGGAAGAUGCUGCGUCGGCGGGGCAGCCCUGGCAUGGGUGUGCAUGUGGGUGCAGCCCUGGGAGCACUGUGGUUCUGCCUCACAGGAGCCCUGGAGGUCCAGGUCCCUGAAGACCCAGUGGUGGCACUGGUGGGCACCGAUGCCACCCUGUGCUGCUCCUUCUCCCCUGAGCCUGGCUUCAGCCUGGCACAGCUCAACCUCAUCUGGCAGCUGACAGAUACCAAACAGCUGGUGCACAGCUUUGCUGAGGGCCAGGACCAGGGCAGCGCCUAUGCCAACCGCACGGCCCUCUUCCCGGACCUGCUGGCACAGGGCAACGCAUCCCUGAGGCUGCAGCGCGUGCGUGUGGCGGACGAGGGCAGCUUCACCUGCUUCGUGAGCAUCCGGGAUUUCGGCAGCGCUGCCGUCAGCCUGCAGGUGGCCGCUCCCUACUCGAAGCCCAGCAUGACCCUGGAGCCCAACAAGGACCUGCGGCCAGGGGACACGGUGACCAUCACGUGCUCCAGCUACCAGGGCUACCCUGAGGCUGAGGUGUUCUGGCAGGAUGGGCAGGGUGUGCCCCUGACUGGCAACGUGACCACGUCGCAGAUGGCCAACGAGCAGGGCUUGUUUGAUGUGCACAGCAUCCUGCGGGUGGUGCUGGGUGCAAAUGGCACCUACAGCUGCCUGGUGCGCAACCCCGUGCUGCAGCAGGAUGCGCACAGCUCUGUCACCAUCACACCCCAGAGAAGCCCCACAGGAGCCGUGGAGGUCCAGGUCCCUGAGGACCCGGUGGUGGCCCUAGUGGGCACCGAUGCCACCCUGCGCUGCUCCUUCUCCCCCGAGCCUGGCUUCAGCCUGGCACAGCUCAACCUCAUCUGGCAGCUGACAGACACCAAACAGCUGGUGCACAGUUUCACCGAAGGCCGGGACCAGGGCAGCGCCUAUGCCAACCGCACGGCCCUCUUCCCGGACCUGCUGGCACAAGGCAAUGCAUCCCUGAGGCUGCAGCGCGUGCGUGUGGCGGACGAGGGCAGCUUCACCUGCUUCGUGAGCAUCCGGGAUUUCGGCAGCGCUGCCGUCAGCCUGCAGGUGGCCGCUCCCUACUCGAAGCCCAGCAUGACCCUGGAGCCCAACAAGGACCUGCGGCCAGGGGACACGGUGACCAUCACGUGCUCCAGCUACCGGGGCUACCCUGAGGCUGAGGUGUUCUGGCAGGAUGGGCAGGGUGUGCCCCUGACUGGCAACGUGACCACGUCGCAGAUGGCCAACGAGCAGGGCUUGUUUGAUGUGCACAGCGUCCUGCGGGUGGUGCUGGGUGCGAAUGGCACCUACAGCUGCCUGGUGCGCAACCCCGUGCUGCAGCAGGAUGCGCACGGCUCUGUCACCAUCACAGGGCAGCCUAUGACAUUCCCCCCAGAGGCCCUGUGGGUGACCGUGGGGCUGUCUGUCUGUCUCAUUGCACUGCUGGUGGCCCUGGCUUUCGUGUGCUGGAGAAAGAUCAAACAGAGCUGUGAGGAGGAGAAUGCAGGAGCUGAGGACCAGGAUGGGGAGGGAGAAGGCUCCAAGACAGCCCUGCAGCCUCUGAAACACUCUGACAGCAAAGAAGAUGAUGGACAAGAAAUAGCCUGACCAUGAGGACCAGGGAGCUGCUACCCCUCCCUACAGCUCCUACCCUCUGGCUGCAAUGGGGCUGCACUGUGAGCCCUGCCCCCAACAGAUGCAUCCUGCUCUGACAGGUGGGCUCCUUCUCCAAAGGAUGCGAUACACAGACCACUGUGCAGCCUUAUUUCUCCAAUGGACAUGAUUCCCAAGUCAUCCUGCUGCCUUUUUUCUUAUAGACACAAUGAACAGACCACCCACAACCUUAGUUCUCUAAGUCAUCCUGCCUGCUGCCUUAUUUCACAGUACAUACAUUUCUUAGGGACACAGUACACUGACCACAUCACCACCCUCUUCUUCCAGUGCUGCGUGGACCAUCUGGCUGCCUUUUUUCUCCAAAAGAUGCAAUAUUCAGACUGACUGACCCCCUGCCUUAUUUCACCAAAGACACGAUGCAUAGUCACCCCGGCCUUGUUUCUCCAAUGGCCGUGAUACACUAGUGAUCAUGUUCAGCCCUGCUUCCACCUGCAUAGAAUCUUUUCUUCUCAGACAGGGACAGUGCGGCCUCAACAUCUCCUGGAGUCUAGAAGCUGUUUCCUUUCCCCUCCUUCCUCCUCUUGCUCUAGCCUUAAUACUGGCCUUUUCCCUCCCUGCCCCAAGUGAAGACAGGGCACUCUGCGCCCACCACAUGCACAGCUGUGCAUGGAGACCUGCAGGUGCACGUGCUGGAACACGUGUGGUUCCCCCCUGGCCCAGCCUCCUCUGCAGUGCCCCUCUCCCCUGCCCAUCCUCCCCACGGAAGCAUGUGCUGGUCACACUGGUUCUCCAGGGGUCUGUGAUGGGGCCCCUGGGGGUCAGCUUCUGUCCCUCUGCCUUCUCACCUCUUUGUUCCUUUCUUUUCAUGUAUCCAUUCAGUUGAUGUUUAUUGAGCAACUACAGAUGUCAGCACUGUGUUAGGUGCUGGGGGCCCUGCGUGGGAAGAUAAAGUUCCUCCCUCAAGGACUCCCCAUCCAGCUGGGAGACAGACAACUAACUACACUGCACCCUGCGGUUUGCAGGGGGCUCCUGCCUGGCUCCCUGCUCCACACCUCCUCUGUGGCUCAAGGCUUCCUGGAUACCUCACCCCCAUCCCACCCAUAAUUCUUACCCAGAGCAUGGGGUUGGGGCGGAAACCUGGAGAGAGGGACAUAGCCCCUCGCCACGGCUAGAGAAUCUGGUGGUGUCCAAAAUGUCUGUCCAGGUGUGGGCAGGUGGGCAGGCACCAAGGCCCUCUGGACCUUUCAUAGCAGCAGAAAAGGCAGAGCCUGGGGCAGGGCAGGGCCAGGAAUGCUUUGGGGACACCGAGGGGACUGCCCCCCACCCCCACCAUGGUGCUAUUCUGGGGCUGGGGCAGUCUUUUCCUGGCUUGCCUCUGGCCAGCUCCUGGCCUCUGGUAGAGUGAGACUUCAGACGUUCUGAUGCCUUCCGGAUGUCAUCUCUCCCUGCCCCAGGAAUGGAAGAUGUGAGGACUUCUAAUUUAAAUGUGGGACUCGGAGGGAUUUUGUAAACUGGGGGUAUAUUUUGGGGAAAAUAAAUGUCUUUGUAAAAA